UCCAGGGCUCAAUGAAUCCUCCCUCCUCAGCCUCCCAAAGUGCUGGGAUUAUAGAUAUGAGCCAUCACACCCUGCCUAAAAUUAUUGACAUGCAUUAUGGUAUAUUUACUCAUGUUAUAGCCCAUCUACCUUUUUUUUUCUUGUAGCUCACCUAGGUUUUGAUGUGUGUCAGCAUUUCUGACUCAGUAUUCCAAACCAGAAAUUGCUUGUGCCUCUUGUGAAAUUUGGUGACCUCAUAGGGCACUUCUACUACCAGCUUUCUUGGUGAAAAUUUCAAGUAAGAACAUAGAAUCUUGGGAUUUGAAGAAGGCUUAAAAUUUAUCUAUCUCAAUGUCGUUAUUAGGUGGUCAUAUCAAUAUAGGUUCAGACACCUCUAGAGGCAGAAAACUCACGGUUUCCUAAGGGAGCUCAUUCCAUUUUGGACAACUCUGAUUAGUUGAGAAUGUUAAACCAAAAUGCUUUCUUGUACCUGCCACCUAGUGGAUCUAUUUCUACCCUCUGGGAACCCUAGAAAAUAUGCAGGAUGUCUCUUUUAUUUGCAGCUGUAAGGUAAUGCAUUUGAAGACCACCAUGAAGGCCCCUGCCCCCAUCUUCUGCCUUUACCUGUGUCUUCCCUACCUCACAUCAAAUAUUCCUCAUCCCCGUGGAGCAGUCCUCACUGUGAGUGCCGCUUCAUUUGCAUACUUGACUAUUUAUUUCUACUCUUUGCUUUACUCUUCAAUCAAGGACUCUAACAUACCAAAAAUGAAUUCAGGGCCAGGCAUGGUGGCUCACACCUGUAACCCCAGCCCUUUGGGAGGCUGAAGUGGGUGGAUCACUUGAGUCCAGGAGUUCAAGACCAGCCUGGCCAACAUGGUGAAACCCCAUCUCUACUAAAAUUGUAAUUAGCCAGGCAUGAUGGUGCAAUGCCUGUAAUCCCAGCUACUCUGGAGGCUGAGGCAGGAAAAUCGCUUGAACCCAGGAGGUGGAGGUUGUAGUAAACUGAGAUUGUGCCGCUGCAUUCCAGCCUGGGCAACAGAGCAAGACUCUGUCACAAGCAAACAAACCACCAGACCAAAACAACAAAUUUAGCUUUUAAACAUCCUUUGGUGUGGAAUCUCAUCAAAAGCUUCCCAUCCAUUAUGUUAUCCAUUCAUUCAGCUAACGUUUAGUUAGUCAUUGCCCUUCUUGAUAGAAAUGCACCACUGAAAAAAAUGCAGUCCUCUGACCUCGAGUGGUUCAACCAGGAGGAACAGACGUAAGCACAGCACAGUCAGUGUUAUAACACAGGUGUGUAUGGAGCCGGGGACACACGGGGGGAAUGAGUGGGAAUCAGACACCGUUUCACAGAGGAAACACUAGAACAGGAUUUUGAAGCAAGAGCAGGAAUUCACCUGCGAGAAGAAGGGAAGGGCACCCCACAUGUGCUAAAAUGCUCAGCAGUUCAAUAGGAUACCCUGCUUUGGAGAACUGUAAGGAGUGUGGGAUGAUCUGAAAAUGGGCUGCAGAGGGGAGGAAGGGAGAGGGAAAGAGCUCUACCUAAGACUCAGAAUCUUGCACUUAAUAGGGGUUCUCACCCCAUUCACCCAACACCCACCAAAUACAGAAGCCGUUUAGUCAGUUAAUAUCUGCAAACCAAACUAAGAGUAACUGAUGAAUGGUGAUUUUAAUUUGGGGUUAAUGUGUAAAUGAGACAUAGUUUCCCUAAAUAACAGCCUGUGGGUCUAGUAGGACAGAUCAAAGGUGAUUUUGCAUAUUUCAGAAGGGCUGGUGACUCUGCUUUUGAAAUACACGGCUGAGUGAUCCAAACAGAAACAUCAGGCUGGUUCUCCUGAACUGAGAAGAGCAGGAGUUCACGUAACAAGGAAUGGCAGAAACGAAGGAUGUUUUUGGCCAGGAACCGCAUCCAGUUGAAGAUGAUUUAUAUAAAGAACGAACGAGAAAAAGAAGGAAAUCAGAUCGAGACCAGCGGUUCCGAGCAUUUCCCUCCAUGGAGCAGAGUGCUCUUAAGGAAUACACCUCCUUUGGAGACCUAGUACUUUAUCCCUGCCAGGUACCUGCAGGUGACAUCUCUCUGUUAAUUCCAGAUGAAAAAUUGGAAUCACGGACCAGAAGGGUUUUGAGCAACACUUAUCAGAAACUUAUUCAGUCUGUCUUCCUGGAUGACAGCAUCCCUAAUGGAGUCAAGUAUCUCAUAAAUAGGCUUCUUGCCUUGAUUGAAAAGCCGACAGUGGACCCAAUCUACAUUGCAUUAUUUGGAAGCACUGGGGCUGGGAAGAGCUCCCUGAUCAAUGCCAUCAUCCAGCAAGCAAUGUUUCUACCAGUGUCUGGAGAAAGCAUAUGUACUUCCUGCAUUGUACAAGUGAGCUCUGGCUGCUGUGUGCAGUAUGAGGCCAAAAUCCACCUUCUGUCUGACCAGGAGUGGAGGGAGGAGCUGAAGAACCUGACCAAACUCCUGCAUAGGACGGAGGAGCUGAGCAGAGAAGAGGCAGAUGCGUGGAACAGGGAUGAGGCAGUGGAGGAAGCCACCUGGAAGCUACAAAUGAUUUAUGGAAAUGGGGCAGAGAGUAAGAACUAUGAGGAGUUACUGAGGGCGAAGCCCAAAAGGAAGAUCCCCACCUCCAGAGUCAUCACCCUCAAGGCGGAAGAGGCAGAAGAGCUGUCCAUCAAGCUGGACCCCUACAUCCGCACACAGAGGAGAGAUUGGGAUGGAGAGGCCGCUGAGAUGCGCAUCUGGCCCUUGAUCAAACAUGUGGAAGUGACACUUCCCAAAUCCGACCUGAUCCCAGAAGGGGUCGUGCUGGUGGACAUCCCAGGCACAGGCGACUUCAACAGCAAGAGGGACGAGAUGUGGAAAAAGACCAUUGACAAGUGCUCAGUGAUCUGGGUGAUCAGCGACAUAGAGCGAGUUUCUGGGGGGCAAGCCCACGAAGACCUUCUGAAUGAGAGCAUCAAAGCCUGCCAGCGGGGCUUCUGUAGGGACGUGGCCCUGGUGGUCACCAAGAUGGACAAACUCCACUUGCCAGAAUACCUAAGGGAAAGAAAGGCAGGAAAUCAAGCUAUUCAGAGUCAGCGAGAGGCUGUUUUAGAAAGAAAUGAAAUGAUAAAACUACAAAGGACUAGAAUUCUCAAGGAAAAACUGAAGAGAAAACUGCCAGCUGACUUCAAGGUUCUGGAAGCCUCAGAUCUGGUGUAUACAGUCAGCGCCCAGGAGUACUGGCAGCAGGCUCUCCUCACCGAGGAGGAAACGGAAAUCCCUAAGUUAAGAGAAUACAUCAGGAAGAGCCUCUUGGACAAGAAGAAGAGGACAGUGACCAAGUAUGUGACUGAAGCCUUUGGCCUGUUGCUCCUCACAGAUAGUUUCAACUCCACGCAAAACCUGCCGAAUGAACACUUGCACAUGAGUGUCCUGCGGAGAUUUGCGGAAGAGAAGGUUGAGCUGCUGGAGAAGGCCAUCGCACAGUGCUUCGCCUGCAUGGAGCAGCCUCUGCAAGAAGGGGUCAGGACCGCCAGGACUUCUUACCGCUGCAUCCUCAGAGCAUGCUUGGUGAGGAGUAAAGGAAACCAAGGUUUUCAUCAGACCCUGAAAGCUGUUUGCCUGAAAAAUGGCAUCUAUGCCUCCAGGACUCUGGCGAGAAUUGAUCUAAAUGAAGCCCUCACUCAGCCCGUCUAUGACCAGAUCGACCCUGUUUUUGGAAGCAUUUUUAGGACGGGGAAGCCCACUGGUUCAGCUCUGAUGCCUCACAUAGAUGCUUUUAAGCAGUCCCUGCAGGAGAAAAUGACAGAAAUUGGGAUAAGAAGUGGCUGGAAAUAUGAUAGCUGCAAAAAAAAUUUCCUGAUCCAGGAGAUAAGUGCCAUCCUCGGGGGCCUGGAGGACCACAUCCUCAGAAGGAAGAGGAGGAUCUACGAGUCCCUCACUGCCUCUGUCCAGAGUGACCUGAAGCUCUGUUACGAAGAGGCAGCUCAGAUCACGGGCAAAAAAGCGUGUGAGCGGAUGAAAGAUGCCAUCAGAAGAGGAGUGGACCGGCAGGUGGCUGAGGGCAUGUUUGAAAGGGCCCAGGAAAGGAUGCAGCACCAGUUUCAGCAGCUGAAGACUGGAAUCGUGGAGAAGGUGAAGGGCAGCAUCACCACUAUGCUGGCCCUUGCUUCGUCCCAGGGGGAUGGCCUCUACAAGGAGCUUGCAGAUGUCGGGAGUGAAUACAAGGAGAUGGAGAAGCUGCACAGAAGCCUGAGGGAGGUCGCGGAGAAUGCACGGCUGAGGAAGGGCAUGCAAGAAUUCCUCCUAAGGGCAUCCCCCAGCAAGGCUGGCCCCCCCGGGACAUCACUGUAACUCCUGGGGCUUAGUCCCAAUGGAUGAAAAAUCAGCCCAGAGCCAGAGAAUUAGAAUUACUUUUUUUGUUCUUAAGAGACAAGAUCUAUCUACCUCUGUUGCCCAGGCUGGAGUGCAGUGGCACCAUCACAGCUCACUGCAGCCUCGAACUCCUAGGCUCAAGCGAUCCUCCAGCCUCAGCCUCCAGAGCAGCUGGGGCUACAGGUACAGGCCACCACACCUGGGUAAUUUUUUUUUUUUUUUUUUUGAGACAGAGUCUCGCUGUGUCACCCAGGCUGGAAUGCAGUGGUGCAAUCUCGGCUCACUGCAACCUCCACCUCCUGGGUUCAAGAAAUUCUCUGCCUCAGCCUCCCAAGUAGCUGGGAUUAUAGGCGACUGCCACCACACCCGGUUAAUUUUUAUAUUUUUAGUAGAGACGGGGUUUCAUCAUCUUGGCCAGGCUGGUCCUGAACUCCUGACCUCGUGAUCCACCCAUCUCUGCCUCCCAAAGUGCUGGGAUUACGGGCAUGAGCCACCGUGCCCGGCCCAUACCUGGGUAAUUUUUUAAUUUUUUGUGGAGAUGGCAUCUUGCUCUGUUGCCCAGGGUGGUCUCAAACUCCUGGCCUCAAGUGAUUCUCUCCCACCUCAGUCUCUUGUGCUAGGAUUGCAGGCAUGAGCCAUUGUGCCUGGCUCAGAAUUCUUUCUGUUUUGUGAAAUCUAAUAGAGGACAUUUCUCAACUAUUUGGACUUUGCAUGCAAUAUAAAACUAGUAUGUUUACUGCAUUUUAUUUUAUAGCCCCAAAGAGUCAUCUUCAAUACCUAAUGGAGUUCUAAAGCUUUAGGGCAAGAAACUUUUGCUUCCGCAAAAACAUCUAAACAUCGCUGGGCAUGGUGGCUCACUCCCGUAAUCCCAGCACUUUGGGAGGCUGAGGCGGGCGGAUCAUGAGGUCAGGAGAUUGAGACCAUCCUGGCUAACACAGUGAAACCCCAUCUCUACUAAAAAUACAAAAAAUUAGCCAGGCGUGGUAGCAUGUGCCUAUAGUCCCAGCUACUUGGGAGGCUGAGGCAGGAGAAUCGCUUGAACCCAGGAGGCAUAGGUUGCAGUGAGCCAAGGUCGCGCCACUGCACUCCAGCCUGGACGACGGAGUGAGACUAUGUCUCAAAAAAAAAAAAAAAAAAAGAAAAAGAAAAAAAUAUAUAUAUAUACACACACACACCCAUACAUAAAAAAACUUAAACAUUAUAGAAAAAACAUUGCACGAUAUAAAACAAGCCAUAAAAAGAAAUUCAUCCUUCAAUAAAGAAAAAUAUCUAAACGUUGAAAAACUUAAGUAUUAUGGAAAACAUUGCAAAAUAAAGCUUUUAGGAAUCCAA